GAGUUGGAGAGGUCCACAGGGGAUUCCAGUUCUCCUAGAAAUCAAGACUGCAGGAAGCAGGCACGAGGGAGUGAGCAAGCACUUGGGAAAGGGCCUGAGCAAAGCAGGCUGAAGCUUGUAUGCUACUGUUUGUUGUAACUGCGGGUGGAGUUAGAGGUAAGGUAAGAGAAGUAAGCUGGGAGAAAAGGAUGGCCGAUACACUCCACCUCCAAAACCUUAAGCUUAAAUCUUCCCACUGGCCCCAUGAUAGCCCCUUACUUUCUUCCCUUCAUUUCCAAUCCACUUGCCAUUACUUAAGCCAUUCCUUUGCCAAACUCCAUCUCACUUGUCCCUGUAUCCUCCUUGCAUGGCCCCCGCAGAGCUGCACCUCAGCCCUGGACCACUCCAGCCCUCUGUUUUCUCCUUGUCUGUACUUAGGUUGCCGUGUCAGACCCCAGCAUUUCAAUACCUCCAAAUGAACAUUUAUGGACUCCAAUCUCAACUAGUCCAUAUGUAAACCCCACUCAUCUUUUUGGCUCUCUUUCAGCUGUCUCUCCAAUUCUACCGGGUAGCUUUUCCACAUGCUCUCCGUUUUCUAAGUCCACGUAGUUUUUACUCUCAGCACAUGAUUUGACCUCCUGUUUCACAAAGGACUUAAAAAUCAUUAGAUAACUCCCUCAGUUUUCUCCUAUCAACUCUAUACACUGAACUGCAUUGCUAUCUGAUUUUUUUCUCUUUUCUUUCUGUUACAAUGGAAGAGGCAGUCCCAUUCCUGCCUCAGGCCAAUUUCUAUGCUUAAGCUUUUGAACUAGCGUCUUCAACAUCAUUACCUGACCAAAUAAUCCUAUUGUUUUUUGUAUCCUCAUUUUCUACAGCAUUUGAUUAUAUUCAAGUCACUCCCAGGUUAAACCAUGACAAAAGGACUGUCUUUGACACAAGUCCUUCUCCAGAUACUGCUCCAGCUCUUCUCUCCAUCACAGGUAUAGUGAACAACUAUAGAGCAGUUUUUUACAAAAUCAUCCAGACUUCUAGGUAAGUGACUGCCUGGGGUCAGAGGGUGAACAGGAGAGAAGAGGGAGGGGAGAGAAACUGGGAAUGACUGCUAAUGGUUGUGGAGAUUCUUCCAUGGAUAAUGAAAAUACUCUAAAAUUGAUUAUGCUGAUGGUUGCAAAACUCUUAUCAACAUACUAAAAACCAUUGAAUUGCACACUUUAAAUGAGUGAAGGCUAUGAUAUGUGAAUUAUACCUCAAAUCAAGCUGUUUUUAAAAAAUAGCUUACUUGGCCGGGCACGGUGGCUCAUGCCUGUAGUCCCAGCACUUUGGCAGGCUGAGGCAGAUGGAUCACCUGAGGCCAGGAGUUUGAGACCAGCCUGGCCAACAUGGUGAAACCCCAUCUCUACUAAAAAAUACAAAAAUUAGCCAGGUGUGGUGGUGGGCACCUGUAAUCUCAGCUACUCAGGAGGUUGAGGCAGGAGAAUUGCUGGAACCUGGAAGGUGGAAGUUGCAGUGAUCCGAGAUCAUGCCACUGCCCUCCAGCCCAGGCUGACAACAGUGAGUCUCCAUCAAAAAAAAAAAAAAAAAAAAGUUUACUUUUGGCACAAUGAAAGACAUAGUUAGGGGAUAUCAUGAGGCAGUCUUUUUAUGGUGAUGGGUCAGUUCUGUAUCCUGAUUAUGGUGAUGGUUACUUGCAUCUACCUGUGGGAUAAACGUUCACAGUACUAUACGCUUCUGAAAUAUAAAUAAAUAUUUUUUUUAAAAGAGCGUGUAAAAACAAACUGGGGAAAUCCAAAUAAGGUCUGUACCUAAGUUUACAGUAUUGUAUAAUACUAAUGGUAAUGUUCUGGAUUUGACAUGUACUAUAGUUAUGUAAGACAUUGCCAUUGGGGGAAGCUGGGUGAAGGGUACAUGAGAACUCUUGGUACUAUUUUUGAAGCUUCUUGUGAAAUUUAAACUAUUUCAAAAUGAAAACGUUACUUUAAAAUUUUGUUUCAGACUUCUCCCUUCUCCUUUCCAAACCACAGGGAGUCCCUUUUUCAAACAAAUAUAUUCCUAGACAUGGUUGAAUGAUCCAGAGGUGGGCACCUGACCCAGCCCAGGUUCAUUGGAAUUUUUUCCUGGAUUUUUUUUUUAACUUGUGUAUUUUUCCAUUAUAUCGUUAUACUACAACUGUUAGUCCAUUCUUCUGUUGAUGAAUUUUUUGGAGUGUUUCCAGUUUUGAGCUAUUAUGAAUAAAGCACUGUAAAAAUUCUUUUUUUUUCUUUUCUCUUUGCAGAACUUACAAUCUGUGAAGAUUCUCAUACAAGUCUUUUGGGAGACAUUUUUUUUUUUUUCAUUGCUCUUGGGUAAAUAACUAGAAAUAAAAUUCCUGAGGCAUAUAGUUAUUUACUUUGUUAGAAACUGCUGAACAGUACUACAAAGCAAUCAUACCAUUUUAUACUCCAACCAGCAAUGUAUGAGAGUUCUGUUUUGUUUCAUAUUCUCACCAAUAUGUGAUAUAGCUAGUCUUUGGUUUUAGCCUUUUUAGAGAGUGUGAAAUACUGUCUCAUUUUGGUUUUAUUUUGCAUUUCCCUGAUGUGUAAAGAUGUUUACCAAUUUUUCAUGAGCUUUAUUGGCCAUUUGUAUAUCUUCUUUCCUGAAAUGUUGGUCAAAUGUUUGACAUUGGAAGACCAAUAAUGCAACCAUAUAAGUGGCUUCUUCAACAGGGCAUACCCUGCAUUUUACCUAUCAUAUAGUAGAUUAAAACCAAGACAAGAAAAGCACACAGCAGUUAAAGCUUGACAUUGAUAUAUCCUGGGGUUAAGUUGAAUGUUUUAGUGAAAUUUUAUGGAAGGGCUCCCCUUCUGCCUUCUUACCAGCCAUUGGCGCCAAAGUACCUUUGCCACAUAUUCUUGGGCAGCUCCCCCAUUUUAUAGGUUUCAGAGCUGUGAAACAGAUGCUUGGGCUGCAGCUGCUUGUGUGGCUGUUUCUGAACUUAUCCUUCCUCCACUCCUACCAGGCAGGCUACAGAGUCCUGACAAUGAAUAGCUCUUGCUUGUCCUGCCAAGUUUUCUUCAUGGCUGGAGAGAGACUUCACCUCCUACUUCCUGUCCUAUAAUUCAGCUGUUUAUUUUUCCUGAGUGCAUGGAUAAACAAACAAAUGAAUAAAUCAACAAGAAGCUAAGCCAUCAGGACUUGAGUGCAAACCCAUCAUGAUAGUAACUGGCAUCUCUAUGAAGCACUGUAGUUUAUAACAUGUUUUUACAUAUAAAAUUUAUUUUUGUCUUCAAAACAAAGUCAUGGGGCAUUAUUAUCAUCUCCAUUUUACAGAUGAGGAAAAUUAAGGCUCAGGGAGGUUAAAUGAGUUGGCUAUGGUCAUCCUCCUUGGCUGUUGUUCCUGAGAAGGGAAAGCUGUGCCUGGGAUUCACAAAUAAUGACAUGGCGGAGACAACCCAGUCUCUAUUAGCACAGACUAGUGUUGGGAGGGAGGCAGGUGGGGACGCAGAGGGCGAGGGGACCAAGGGAGCCUGAGGUGCUGGAUUCCUUUAACUCCCAAAAGUGCUAACCUAGGGUAGCUCAGGGCACAAGGGCAGGUCUUUGUGUGGUAUGAAUUGAGAAGUCUUGCCAGGAACUCCUACCAGAAUCUACUUCCCUGGCUAUACAGAGUACCUCAGUUUUCAUAAUCAUUCCUCUCCUCCUAACUAGGACAGUACUGCUUAAACUUUCCCAUUGAAGUUUUCCAAUUGCUGAGGCCAUUUAGUCGUUAGGGAUGAUUGGAGUCUCCACCACUGAAGCCAGGAACCCCAAAUCUGUUAGGACUCCCCAGAAGCUGCCAGAGAAUUGCUGCACUGAAGAGUCUUAGGAGCAGGCAACUGAUUUGAGGGGUAGGGGACCAGGCCAUAGAGUUUUAUUUGUAUAGCACAGAAAUUGCUUGCAUAUAGAUUGUGUUUUUAUUUUGGGGACUGAUAGAGAUUAUGACAGGUGCCAAGUUCCCUUCAAGCCCCUCCUGGAAAUAACAGUACAACUUACAUGUAGUCAUUCUUGGUAUCCCUGGGAAGAGAUGGAGAAUUAUUCAGUACAUUUCUUCUUAGUGACAAGAAAUUUCUAAGGUCAUUAUACAAUAGUACCCACACUUAACCAUCCACUGGGUCAGUAGGGUACUGCAGUUAAGAGUUAGGCUUCAGAAUGUAACAAACUUAGGUUAUGCCCCUUCCUAUUAUUCUACCAGUCAUACCAUACAAGGUCAGUGCGUAUUAACUACAUUAUUAUUACUGGUGGAGAAAAUAUAAAGUGACAAAAAACCACUUUGGACUUAGUUAACUUAUAUUAAUUUGCAUUUUAGAAAUUACAACAGCACCUACAAACAUUUGACAGAUAGUGGUAUAAAAAUCUGUGAGUGGUGUUAUUUUUCCAGACCACGGACAAUGCUUUGUAUCCAGAUUGAUUUGGACCUGUUGCAAUGAUUGCUCUGCAGAGGCAUUUGUCCAUCGUGCUGGCACUUCGAUACAGUGGAAGAGCAUGGAUUUUGGAAUCUUACAGGCCUAGAUUCAAAUCCUGGCUCUGUCACAUGCUAACUGUGCCAUCUUUGACAAGUUACUUAGCUUCUCUGAGUCACAGUUUCCUCAUCUCUAAAAUAAGGGAUAAUACCUGCCUCACAGGGCCAGUGGAGGAUUGAGUCAUAUAAUAUCCAUAGGAACCUGACUAAUGUUGGGUGUCAAAUAAAUGUUCAAUUGUUCUCUCACAGCUUGAGUGAACAGAACAAUCCACAUCAGUUUGAAAACAAUUUUGGUUGAGUUGCAGAAGCCUGGACAUUAAGGACCUCAUACCUAGAAGGACUCGUAGCCCCACUAACUGAGAGCAGAAGGAUAAGUAUUCUUCACAUUCAACAGUGCUUUAAAUGUUUUAUUAACAAUGUCUUCUUCCAGUGCAUGUAGGGAGAGCCCCAGCCUCCACCUACUCUCUUUUACCUAACUUAUCAUUCGUAACUUCUUAAUCUCCCUUUCUUGAGCUUUCUCAUUGCACUUAGCCUGGAAGCCUCAGGUAAGUGGCUCUACUCACCCUGCAGUGAAGUGGGUCACGGGCACAAUGUCGCUGGGUCAUAGACUAUGGGUUUCUAAGGCCUGCCUCAGGGCAGUUAGACUCCUGCAAUAUCCCUUAUUCAAGAGUGGUCCUGACUGCAGUGUUGAUGGUGGUGGAGCAGACCCUCCAUGGGUCACUUUCCUGAGAGUCAGGUAGGAAUCAUCCAUUGGCUCAGAACAGCCCUGCCACUCUUCCAGGGAUGGAAGGCUAGAGGCCAUGCCAGAGACGUCUGUUCUACAAGCAGGAAGGCAGGCAGGGCAGAAGUGAAUGCCAGUGGACUGUGCAGACCUCAGCUUGGGGAGGGCAUGUUCUCCUGGGAGUGGAGGUGGUUUUAUUGCCAGGGAGCUGGGAAGUUGCCUGUGGUUUUGUCUUCCUGUUCCCUGUACAGCUGCCUUCCACCUUUCUUCACUCAGUGGAUGUGGGGGAGGACUGUGUGCAGUCUGAGAAACUGGACACGCUUGUGGAAGGACCCAGACCAGACUUCUUCCUCCCCUCAGCGCAAUGUGCUUUGCCUGUUUCAAGAACGUCCCUUCCAUUUCCUGUUCCUGGGGCUGCACAAUAUGCUUCCUCUCUUCCUUUGGACAUAAGCCUGAAGAAAGAUACUCUCUUCUUGAAGAAGUUUUCAUCCCUGGCUAUAAUCUUUUUUCCCAUAUCCUUAGCAAGUAUGGGCAAAUGAGCACUCACGUUGCUACUCCCUGGUUUUGCAUUGAUCUCCUAGAGCAGGUGGCCACACUUGCACCUUUUUCUCAGAAGUGGGAUUGGAGUAAGGAGCCAAGUUCACCUAUCAUGAUCAUGUGACAUAGUGGUUUGAGAUCAUGUGACAUACUGGUACGGGGAUCAUAUGACAUUGGAAUGGGAACAAAAAGCAGGAGACCCAAUAUUUCAGCCUAUGUUACAGGACAAAGGCCGUCGCUUUGUAAAAGCUUGAAGUGCAGUUUGCUGCUGAGUACAGAAGACCUUUGCAAACAGAGAGGGGAGAUUUUCUCUGUAAGGUUGCAAACAAGAGCAGGUCCUGGAAGAUAAGAUUCCCCGCCAUGUUAUCCUCCGUGGUGUUUUGGGGACUAAUUGCCCUCAUUGGCACUUCCAGGGGCUCAUACCCCUUCAGUCACUCAAUGAAGCCUCACCUACAUCCACGCCUGUACCACGGCUGCUAUGGGGACAUCAUGACCAUGAAGACCUCUGGGGCCACUUGUGAUGCAAACAGUGUGAUGAACUGCGGGAUCCGUGGUUCUGAAAUGUUUGCUGAGAUGGAUUUGAGGGCCAUAAAACCUUACCAGACUCUGAUCAAAGAAGUCGGGCAGAGACAUUGCGUGGACCCUGCUGUCAUCGCAGCCAUCAUCUCCAGGGAAAGCCAUGGCGGAUCUGUCCUGCAAGACGGCUGGGACCACAGGGGACUUAAAUUUGGCUUGAUGCAGCUUGAUAAACAAACGUACCACCCUGUCGGUGCCUGGGAUAGCAAAGAGCACCUUUCACAGGCUACUGGGAUUCUAACAGAGAGAAUUAAGGCAAUCCAGAAAAAAUUCCCCACGUGGAGUGUUGCUCAGCACCUCAAAGGUGGUCUCUCAGCUUUUAAGUCAGGAAUUGAAGCGAUUGCCACCCCAUCGGACAUAGACAAUGACUUCGUCAAUGAUAUCAUUGCUCGAGCUAAGUUCUAUAAAAGACAAAGCUUCUAGGCAAAGCUCUGUGGGUGGGCCAGGUUGGCAGAGUGCUCAGAUGGCCGCCUUUGAGAGUUUUACGUGAAUGUGUUGUAUACAACACUGGCAAAGAAAUGAUUAAAAUCAUGAAAGAAAA